AUCACUACUGUGACUGCUUGUACCCGAUAAUCUUGCUCUGCAGCUCCCUCAGUGAACAACUUACUGAGGUGCCUUUCUUUUUACAAGAGGAUGUCAGCUCUGAGCUCCAGCAAGAAAUAACAGACUUCACCUUGGAAUAGCUCAUCUUACUCCUGCAUCAUUAAAGCGGAUUUUCAAAAGAAAACAAAAAUCAAGUCCCCUUUCCAGUUCCACUUUCUUCCAGCAUUGAACAGGAACAGUUUCACGCUCCAGAGAUGCUGCUUAAAUUCAUUGGACAGUGCUGAGUUCUUACAUGAAGAAAGAAACAGCCCAAAUGGAAAGAAGAGUAUUGAUAUGGUUUGGCUGUGCCUCCACCCAAAUCUCAUCUUGAAAUCCCACCUAUUGUUGGAGGGACCCAGUGGACUCAACCACAGCAAUAUGUAAGAAGAACACACACCAAACAUUCCUGAAGUGAUUUAAAAGAUGGAAUCUCGCUCUGUCUCCCAGGCUGGAGUGCAGUGGCGCAAUCUCAGCUCAUUGCAACCUCCACCUCCUGGGUUCACGCCAUUCUCCUGCCUCAGCCUCCUGAGUAGCUGGGACUACAGGCGCCCGCCACCACGCCAGGAUAGACUGAAGAGGAGCAAGAACAGAAACAGGGAGCCAGUUACAGAUCUAUCCCAAGAAUUCUGGGGAGAGAUGAUGGUGUCUGCAGCAGAGUGACAGCAGUGGAGAUUGAGAGAAAAGGUUGAAAAUGGUUGCUUGUGUUCAACUACUGUGAAGAGUUGGAAUCAGACAACUACGGCUUUGAUUUUCCAAGUGGUUCAGAAUGUAAAUAUGAUCUGACCUUUCCCUGAUGGACAGUUAAAUCAUGGACACGCUAAACAAUUUACUUUGGACUGUCCUUCCUAAAGAUGCUCUGGCUUCUCUCUUGAAUGCUCACUAAGCUUUCGUAGCUGACAAGGAAAGGAAGGAAAACUGUGAACUGGAAAGUUAUCUUACAAUGAAAAUUACUAGCACAUCUUGCAUCUGUCCAGUCCUAGUGUGUCUCUGUUUUGUGCAGAGGUGUUAUGGAACUGCUCACCACAGCUCCAUCAAGGUGAUGAGAAACCAAACCAAACACAUUGAAGGUGAAACCGAAGUCCAUCAUCGUCCCAAAAGGGGAUGGGUAUGGAAUCAGUUCUUUGUUUUAGAAGAACAUAUGGGACCAGAUCCUCAGUAUGUUGGAAAGCUGCACUCCAAUUCUGACAAAGGUGAUGGAUCUGUCAAGUACAUCCUUACUGGAGAGGGUGCUGGGACUAUAUUUAUCAUUGACGAUACCACGGGUGAUAUCCACUCAACAAAAAGCCUAGACAGAGAGCAGAAGACCCACUAUGUGCUUCAUGCUCAAGCUAUUGAUAGACGUACAAACAAACCUCUUGAGCCUGAAUCCGAGUUCAUCAUCAAAGUGCAAGACAUCAAUGACAACGCUCCAAAAUUCACAGAUGGACCAUACAUUGUUACUGUGCCUGAAAUGUCAGAUAUGGGUACCUCUGUUCUACAGGUGACAGCUACUGAUGCAGAUGACCCUACCUAUGGAAACAGCGCUCGGGUGGUUUACAGCAUUCUCCAAGGACAACCCUACUUCUCCGUCGACCCUAAAACAGGAGUUAUUAGAACGGCCUUACAUAACAUGGACAGAGAAGCCAGAGAACAUUACUCCGUAGUCAUUCAAGCCAAAGACAUGGCUGGGCAAGUUGGAGGGCUUUCAGGAUCUACAACAGUCAACAUCACCUUAACCGAUGUCAAUGACAACCCACCACGCUUUCCUCAAAAACACUAUCAGCUAUAUGUUCCUGAGUCAGCUCAAGUUGGUUCAGCUGUUGGGAAAAUCAAGGCAAAUGAUGCUGACACUGGCUCAAAUGCUGACAUGACCUACUCCAUCAUAAAUGGUGAUGGCAUGGGAAUAUUCUCAAUCUCCACUGACAAAGAGACCAGAGAAGGAAUCCUUUCUUUAAAGAAGCCACUGAACUAUGAGAAAAAGAAGUCAUAUACCCUCAACAUAGAAGGAGCAAAUACACAUCUUGAUUUUCGCUUUUCUCACUUGGGUCCUUUUAAAGAUGCUACUAUGCUGAAGAUCAUUGUUGGGGAUGUAGAUGAACCACCACUAUUUUCCAUGCCUUCCUACCUCAUGGAAGUCUACGAAAAUGCCAAGAUUGGGACCGUCGUUGGUACAGUUUUGGCACAAGAUCCUGACAGUACUAACAGCUUAGUAAGAUACUUCAUCAACUACAAUGUUGAAGACGACAGAUUUUUCAACAUUGAUGCCAAUACUGGGACCAUUAGGACUACAAAGGUUCUCGACAGAGAAGAAACUCCAUGGUACAACAUCACAGUCACUGCUUCAGAAAUUGAUAAUCCUGAUUUGCUGAGCCAUGUCACAGUGGGUAUUAGAGUUCUGGAUGUCAAUGACAAUCCACCCGAACUUGCCAGGGAAUAUGAUAUUAUUGUAUGUGAAAAUUCUAAGCCUGGCCAGGUUAUUCAUACCAUCAGUGCCACUGAUAAAGAUGAUUUUGCCAAUGGACCAAGGUUUAACUUCUUUCUUGAUGAACGCCUGCCUGUAAAUCCAAACUUCACUCUGAAGGACAAUGAAGAUAACACAGCCAGCAUUCUGACAAGGCGGAGGAGAUUUAGUCGAACUGUUCAGGAUGUGUAUUAUCUGCCCAUUAUGAUCUCUGAUGGUGGAAUCCCCUCUCUCAGCAGCAGCAGCACCCUCACCAUCAGGGUUUGUGCAUGCGAGAGAGAUGGGCGUGUGCGGACCUGCCAUGCAGAAGCCUUCCUGUCCUCGGCUGGUUUGAGUACAGGAGCCUUAAUCGCUAUUCUUCUCUGUGUUCUCAUUCUCCUGGCAAUUGUGGUACUUUUUAUCACCCUGAGGCGCAGCAAAAAAGAGCCCUUGAUCAUUUCAGAAGAGGAUGUACGGGAGAACGUGGUCACCUAUGAUGAUGAAGGAGGCGGAGAGGAAGACACAGAGGCCUUUGACAUCACAGCCUUGAGGAAUCCUUCUGCUGCUGAGGAGCUCAAGUACCGGAGGGAUAUCAGACCUGAAGUGAAGCUCACUCCCAGACACCAGACAUCAUCCACCCUGGAAAGCAUAGAUGUUCAGGAAUUUAUUAAGCAAAGACUGGCAGAAGCAGACCUAGACCCUAGCGUUCCCCCUUAUGACUCUCUUCAGACUUAUGCCUAUGAGGGUCAGAGAUCAGAAGCUGGGUCUAUCAGCUCGCUGGAUUCAGCAACGACACAAUCAGACCAGGAUUAUCACUACCUUGGAGACUGGGGACCCGAGUUUAAAAAGUUAGCUGAACUCUAUGGAGAAAUAGAAUCUGAAAGAACAACUUAGGGGGUCAGUUCUUGCAACCUUGUGGAAUUUGCUUCCUGAGUAAGUGGAUAUACAACCUCAGCAAUGACAAGGAAGAAGUGUGGAAACAGUACUUGGAACUGAGGAAGCUGGACACAGCUCCUGUAGAAACAAGUGCCCUUUUCAUGAUCGAAACUGGGUUAUUUAAUUGGAAGAAAGUAAAAAAAAAAAAAAAAAGACAAUACAAAGAAAAAGUUAUUGUUCCUUGUGUAUAUUUUCAAUUGCUCAAUAAAGUCUGUGGUACUGUUUAUUAAGAAUACCUGAAUUAAGCCAAACAAUGAUAUUUGUUUCAAUAUAUUGUGAUUUAUUUUUUUCAAAAGCAAAACUAAACAGAAAGGCUCAAGAUCACUGGUGGUUAUGACUUAUAGGGGUGGUAACACUAAUACAGGAAACUUGUGAAGGUAAUCACAACCUCUUUUAUCACUUUUCUGGGUGAAACCUUGAGAACCACACUCUGUUAUUAUAACAGAUCUCAUUAGCCUUGUCUUGUGUUUAUAUUACAUGAGGUAUUUCCACUCUAUCAUGGACUUGUAUGUACCAUUUCCCUUUGCCCUCCCCAGUUCUUUUCUCCAUACAAAACUGAUGGAGCAUGGGGAUUUGCUGCCUGCACUAUAAUGUAUGCAACUUCAGUGCACCAGUUGUGUGCUGUACUGAGCACGAGACUAUUGUCUCUAUCCCGUACACCCCCUUUUAUUUUAAUGGGAUACUCCUAUUUUUAAAUGGACAGAAAGAAUAGUUUAAGGUAUGUUAUGAAAAUCUGAUAUGUCAGGGAAUAAUUUAAUUUUAAAAAUAGCCACACACCUUAUCUUCUACCAAAUGUUGGGGAACUUUUUUUUUCCUUUUUUCCACUUGUUUUAUUAUAUUUAAAUCAGCAAUUUUGGUCAUUUCUCUAUUUAAAAUUAAUUGUCAAAUAUUUUGCUGGCUGGUUUGUACUUCAGUCUAAUUCACUUAUUUUCAACACGAGCAGUAAUUAAAAAUAAGUACCUCACACAAUAACAAUGUAGUCUGAAAGACUAUCCUCCAAUGAACGUAAAUGUCAUAGAAUCAUAGUUGACUUACAUUUAUUCCUUACACAGUUUCAGAUUUUUUCCAUCUCACUGAUAAUUAGUUUGGUAUCAACAGGAAAAUGUGUAGGACUAGGAGCAAAAAAGGAGAUUCACAGUUAUUAUCCUCAGAUAUGUUUCCGAAAGUCUCUGUGUUCAGGGUCCAAACCACAAAGUAGAGAUGGCAAUGACUUCCCUGCCCACCUCACAGGGUUGUUGUGAGGAUUAAAUGAGCAUCUGUAAAAUGCUUUGCCAACUGCAAAGUAUUCAAUUGCAUAAAAGCUUGCAGACGCUUAUCUAAUUUUCUAGUUUCAUUAGCUUAUAAAUAUAUAUUUACAUGCAUCUGGCAUAAAAUAUUAUCACAGGAGAAUUUCAUGAAAUCUUCAACAGUGAAGCUACUGUUUAAAUAUAUGUACACAAUUCCAAUUAUUUUAAUAUUUUCAUAAGCUAAUUUCUGAGAAUUUGGGUGGGGCUUUUUUUUUCAAAUUGUUUUAGAUAAUGUUUUGUUGUUGUUGCUAUUGGCCUUGAAGUAAGAAUUCAUACCAUAAUGGUCCUAUUUUCUAAAACUGGCCACAUCUAUAUAUUUCAGAAAUAUUGAAAUUCUUAAAUACAUGAAAUAGGAAUUAGUUGACACCGGAGUUUUUCCUUUGCUCUUUAAAUUUAUCAUUAUCAGUGUCCCCAAAAGUUAUAUGACAUUUUCUGUCUGUUUCUACCCAUGUGCAAAAUUUUGGAUUUUACCUCUGUUUGCAAUUGCCCUGUGCUAUCAUAUUAUAAUUUGAGGUAUGGGAAGUAAGUAAGCUUAAUUUGAAUAAUUCUCAAUUUGUGUUUUAAGCCUGAGGAAUAAAAUGUAAUUUAAGCUUUUUACGACA